AUUCCCUUCGUGCCGCUACCAAGAUGGCGGCGCCCAUCUUGCGGUCCUUUUCCUGGGGCCGGUGGUCUGGUACCCUAAAUCUCUCAGUAUUGUUGCCCUUGGGGCUGCGUAAGGCCCACUCGGGCGCUCAGGGGUUACUGGCAGCGCAGAAGGCUCGAGGUCUGUUCAAGGACUUCUUCCCGGAGACGGGGACGAAAAUAGAGCUCCCAGAGCUCUUCGACCGUGGCACGGCGAGUUUUCCCCAAACCAUUUACUGUGGCUUCGACCCCACGGCAGACUCGCUUCAUGUGGGUCAUCUACUUGCGCUGCUGGGCCUGUUUCAUUUGCAGCGAGCGGGCCACAACGUGAUCGCGCUGGUGGGAGGCGCCACGGCGCGCCUGGGAGACCCGAGCGGCCGUACCAAGGAACGCGAGGCGCUGGAGACAGAGCGCGUGCGAGCCAACGCGCGAGCUCUGCGCCUAGGGCUUGAGGCCCUGGCGGCUAAUCACCAGCAGCUUUUCACUGAUGGGCGCUCCUGGGGCAGCUUCACUGUGCUGGACAACUCGGCCUGGUACCAGAAGCAGCACCUGGUGGACUUCCUGGCGGCAGUGGGGGGUCACUUCCGCAUGGGGACGCUGCUGAGCCGGCAGAGCGUGCAGCUGCGGCUCAAGAGCCCCGAGGGCAUGAGCUUGGCCGAGUUCUUUUACCAGGUGCUCCAGGCCUAUGACUUCUAUUACCUCUUCCAGCGUUAUGGAUGCAGGGUCCAGCUGGGCGGAUCUGAUCAACUAGGCAACAUCAUGUCCGGAUAUGAGUUCAUCAACAAGUUGACUGGAGAAGAUGUAUUUGGAAUCACCGUUCCUCUAAUUACAAGUACAACUGGAGCAAAGCUGGGAAAGUCUGCUGGCAACGCUGUUUGGCUAAACAGAGAUAAGACAUCUCCAUUUGAAUUGUAUCAAUUCUUUGUCAGGCAACCGGACGAUUCAGUGGAAAGGUACCUGAAGCUGUUCACUUUCCUGCCCCUUCCAGAGAUUGAUCAUAUCAUGCAGCUGCAUGUCAAAGAGCCAGAAAGGCGGGGUCCUCAGAAACGACUGGCAGCAGAAGUAACAAAGCUUGUUCAUGGACGAGAAGGAUUGGAUUCUGCUAAAAGGUGUACACAAGCCCUUUAUCACAGUAGCAUAGAUGCACUGGAGGUCAUGUCUGAUCAGGAGUUAAAAGAGUUGUUUAAAGAAGCUCCAUUUUCUGAAUUUUUUCUCGAUCCUGGAACAAGUGUCCUAGAUACUUGCCGCAAAGCAAAUGCCAUUCCAGAUGGUCCCCGAGGGUAUCGAAUGAUAACAGAAGGCGGAGUCAGCAUAAAUCACCAACAAGUAACAAAUCCUGAGAGUGUUUUAAUUGUUGGACAACAUAUUCUCAAGAAUGGACUUUCCUUACUUAAAAUAGGAAAAAGAAAUUUCUACAUUAUAAAAUGGCUUCAGUUGUGAUGAAAAGUCCUUCUGGUUGUCCAAAUAAACUUACCCAUCAUUCAUUCUCAAGACCUCUGAAGGGUUGGCUCCAGAACUUAGACCUUUGCUUAUGCAAAUCAGAAAAACAGAAUGGACUAGGACUCAGUGUGAGUAACUUCAUUAUUUUUAUGGGCCGGUUAAUAAAUAUUUGUUUAAUAAUGGGAUGUUUUAUUUUCUGAUGUACAAAGCUUGAUUACCAUAGAAAACCAUGAUUUUCAGGGUUAAUCUCUUUUUAAAAUUAUACUUCAGAAGAGAAAGAAAUGCUGCUUUCCUAUCUUACCCUUCCUGCUCUCCUUUUUGUAGUGAUGAGGAACAAUGAAAAAGAGGUAGUGUAAGGAAUUGUGAGGCUGGGCAUGGUGGCUCACACCUGUAAUCCCAGCACUUCGGGAGGCCAAGGUGGGCAAAUCGCUUGAGGCCAGGAGUUUGAGACCAGCCUGGCCAACAGGGCGAAACCCCGUCUCUACUGAAAAUAUAAAAAUUAGCCAGAUGUGGUUGCAGGCACCUGUAACCCCAGCUACUCAAGAGGCUGAGCUGCGAGAAUCACUUGAACCCAGGAGAUGGAGGUUGCAGUGAGCUGAGAUCACGCCACUGCACUCCAGCCUGGGAGACAGCAUGAGUAGUGAGUGAAACUCUGUCUCA